AUGCAAAGGGACAAAGGCCAGCUCCGGGUUCGGCCGGGGCCUCCGCCCAUCCCUCGGGGCUACCUGUUGCUGCAGGCGCAGCGCAACUCGGUCCAGGGGCUCCGAGGAAGAAUUCCCAGCUCCAGCAUCGCGCCCACCUUCUCAGGCCCCGAACUUCCCCUAAUCUCAAACUGCGAAGAGGAGGGCUCCCGCUGGGUCCGGAAUGUGGUGGCGGUAGGUCCCUGCACCCGCCCGGCGACUCCUUGCCAAGGUCUCUCCUCCAGAGCAGAACAAAGACGCCGCGAGGAGAGCUUCUGUCCUCGCCUCCCCCGCCCCGCGCUUCACUCGCACCAGCCCACGCCGCUCUCGGAAACUUUACAACCAACUUCCCCUAGAGUUCGUGCGCGCGGCGAGUGGGCCAGAAGGAGAAACCGGGACAAUCGCAUCCCGGGACCAGAGAUGCCCUCUUCCGCGUCCCCUCCUGGACAGGGAGCACCACCUCUUGCACCGCCCGUCCCAGUCUGCGAGCUGGGCGACCCGCGGUGCCAGGGCGAGCGGAGCACGCGCUUUUCCCAGCCCCUUAAGCGAAUGAUGUUUCUUUAGUCUGGACGCGUACA